ACUUCCAGAAAGCUGUGGGCCCUGGGAUACUCCCCUCCCAGGGUGUCUGGUGGCAGGCCUGUGCCUAUCCCUGCUGUCCCCAGGGUGGGCCCCGGGGGUCAGGAGCUCCAGAAGGGCCAGCUGGGCAUAUUCUGAGAUUGGCCAUCAGCCCCCAUUUCUGCUGCAAACCUGGUCAGAGCCAGUGUUCCCUCCAUGGGACCUAAAGACAGUGCCAAGUGCCUGCACCGUGGACCACAGCCGAGCCACUGGGCAGCCGGUGAUGGUCCCACGCAGGAGCGCUGUGGACCCCGCUCUCUGGGCAGCCCUGUCCUAGGCCUGGACACCUGCAGAGCCUGGGACCACGUGGAUGGGCAGAUCCUGGGCCAGCUGCGGCCCCUGACAGAGGAGGAAGAGGAGGAGGGCGCCGGGGCCACCUUGUCCAGGGGGCCUGCCUUCCCCGGCAUGGGCUCUGAGGAGUUGCGUCUGGCCUCCUUCUAUGACUGGCCGCUGACUGCUGAGGUGCCACCCGAGCUGCUGGCUGCUGCCGGCUUCUUCCACACAGGUCAGUCCCGGGCGGGGGGGCCUUCCUGCCGUGGGCCUGGGCACGAUUCUGGACCCUUCCAGCCCAGGGCUCUGCCUCCUCCGUAGCAUCCAUCCCCCAACAGGAAGGGUCUGGCCUGAUGACGGAGCAGUGGUCCUGCAAGCCCCUCCAGUGCCCAUGGGCUCGUGCCUGACACCCUCCCCCGGAGUCUCUGCUGGCUGAGUGUUUCAGACCGUGGGAUGUGAGGAGGGGCUGCCUCUGGCCACAGUCUGAGGGUCUCAGCUGUGGAGGCCGCCAGCUUGGUGCACAAGUACCCCUUUGUGAUAGAAGUGGGUGGGGCUGACAUUGCCUGGGGCCCUCACCUUCCCCGCUGCUGUUCUGCACAGGGAGAGGAGAUGUUUAAAGAACAGGAUCAGGGUGACCAAGGCAGGCAGUGGUCAGCCAGAAGGUCCUGGAUGCUCAGCCUGUGGGGAAUUUCUCCAGGCCCCAACCUGCAGCUACUGUCUGGUCUUCCCCAACUGAAUCAAGUCCCCGGAGUACCUAUCCUAGUCUUGGCCCGGGCCUGCUCCUCUGCCCUACAGCUGCAGACCAUGUGGUCAGACCUGAGUUCAGGUCCCAGCUCUGCCACUUCCUGGCUGAAGGACAGGGCAGCAGGGCCCACCGAGGGCUUUACAAAUACUGGCACAGCCAUGGUCAUUGUCAGCAGUGGGCUCUGGCGGGGCACCAUCCUGGUAAGGCUGGACCAACUUAAGACAGCUGGUCGGGGGGACAGUGGCUGGGACAGUCAGAAGCCGUGGCGUGAAGGGGCAGGCCCAGCUCACCCACCUCCCUGGAAGUCCAAGGCUCAGGAGGCAAAGGCCAGGCAAGAGGCAUGGCAGGUGCAGAGCCGGGGUCUUUGGGGCUGGUAGAGGUCCAGUGCCCGAUGCAGCCCAAACCUGUGAUGUCAGUGGCAGGUGACGUAUCGCAUGGAUGCCGAUGAGGGGACGGGGUCGCCAGGAGGUAGAGAGAUGACGGGUCCCCCACCCCCAAAGGGAGGCAUGAGUUCCUAAAAGCAAGCCUGGCCCCAGACUGGCCUUCUAGGGCAGCCUCCCUUCUUCUUCUCACUGGGAAUCCAUCUUGGGGAAGCAGAGACCUGGGGAGGGGCCCUUCUGGCUCCUGAAGCCCCAGGGCUAUAGAUGUACCAAGCCCUGGGGGGCCCCCACUGCUCACUCUGGGAACAAUGCAAAUGCCAGCUCAGUCCUUUCCUGAACAUUCUCGCCCAUCCUGGCCGGCACCCCAGUCACCCUUGUCCCCUUUUCACCUUUGAUGCUAAUGAGGUACAAGUGACAUCCCCCACCAAGCCCCCUGCCCACCCCCUCCUCCUUCUUGCCACCUGGGAGCUCCCCUCCAGCUGAAGCUCUCAUAGCCUUGGAAGGACACACCGGGGGCCCGGGGACUGGGUGGGACUUGGCUGGGGCCAGCAUCUCUCCGCACCCCAGGCCAUCAGGACAAGGUGAGGUGCUUCUUCUGCUAUGGGGGCCUGCAGAGCUGGAAGCGCGGGGACGACCCCUGGACGGAGCAUGCCAAGUGGUUCCCCAGCUGUCAGUUCCUGCUCCGGUCAAAAGGAAGAGACUUUGUCCACAGUGUGCAGGAGACUCACUCCCAGCUGCUGGGCUCCUGGGACCCGUGGGAAGAACCGGAAGACGCAGCCCCUGUGGCCCCCUCCGUCCCUGCCUCUGGGUACCCUGAGCUGCCCACACCCAGGAGAGAGGUCCAGUCUGAAAGUGCCCAGGAGCCAGCCCCCAGGAGCCAGGGAUGUGGAGGCGCAGCUGCGGCGGCUGCAGGAGGAGAGGACGUGCAAGGUGUGCCUGGACCGCGCCGUGUCCAUCGUCUUUGUGCCGUGCGGCCACCUGGUCUGUGCUGAGUGUGCCCCCGGCCUGCAGCUGUGCCCCAUCUGCAGAGCCCCCGUCCGCAGCCGCGUGCGCACCUUCCUGUCCUAGGCCAGGUGCCAUGGCCGGCCAGGUGGGCUGCAGAGUGGGCUCCCUGCCCCUCUCUGCCUGUUCUGGACUGUGUUCUGGGCCUGCUGAGGAUGGCAGAGCUGGUGUCCAUCCAGCACUGACCAGCCCUGAUUCCCCGACCACCGCCCAGGGUGGAGAAGGAGGCCCUUGCUUGGCGUGGGGGAUGGCUUAACUGUACCUGUUUGGAUGCUUCUGAAUAGAAAUAAAGUGGGUUUUCCCUGGAGGUA